AGUUGAGUGUUUCUGCCAACCGGGGCCUGGCUUGGCCCACCUUGGCUGAGCUUGCUCUGGUGCUAGGGUCAGCUAGACAGGUCGGCAGGAGACCAGCUGCUCUAGAAGAGCCUGGACAGGAUGAAUUGGUUCUCCUUCCACGUGCAUCUUGCAUCCCUCCAGCCAAGGAUUUGAACCCAGGUCUCGUCUGACUCCAAAUGCACCAAGAGGAUGGAGCCCAGAGUGACACAGAGGAAGAGGCCCCUGGAUGGAUGCAUGGGGAAGAUCACGGGAAUUACAAGUGACAUCCUGAAGUAUGAUCACAAAUGUUUCAAAUUAAGCCUUCCUGCUAAGUUUCCAGAGGUGUGUGGCUCGGACGAAGUGUUUCCAGACCCUGAUCUACUGCAUGUCCUGCCUGUUGCUGGUUCUUUGCAGCAGUCCAUUGACCAAUGCUGUCUACAGCUUGAGAGCCUCUGCAGGCCAGGGCUGCUCUGUGCACAUCCUACGUUACUAUUCAAACUGCACAGCAGCAUGAAAAACAGGCCCUUCUUUUCUCUCAUUUACACAUAUGUGAAGAAGACACAGCAAGUGAGAAAACGUGACCGAAAGCCACGCGGACAGGUGGCCGCAGGGCCAAACCCAACUUCCGUGAUGUGAUCUGGCUACAGUUUGGAGCCCACAUAUUUCAAUAGUUAUCCCCAGGCCUGGCACGUCAAAGAGGCUCCAGAAAUGUUUGCUGAGUGAGUGAUGAAUCAGCAAUUUCUGAUUUUCUCCUAAACUUAGAGAAUAAGUGGCUUGUCUGCAGUCACCCAGGGCGUCCCUGACAGAGGUACAAGUAAAGCCCAGAUCUCUGCAUCUCUGGUUCAAGGCCUUUUGUACUACACACCGCUGUCUCUUUGUCAUCAUUAAAAGCAAGGCUCAAGGGACAUGUUUUCUAGCCUUAGUUCCCCAUCUACAAAAUGGGCCUCAUGGAAUGGAAUGUCUCCACUUCACUCCAGCAUCAACAAGUGGGGAAUUCUGAUGGAUUCAAUUCGACUUCUUUCCAUGGGCGUGUUCUAAGCAGCCUCUUUGUUCCAGAAGCUGCCCUCAGCCAGAGUUGGAUAAGCCAAUCCUCACUCCCCAGCCUCCUCUGGAUAGGGAUGAAGACCCCACUGGGGUUGGAAGUGCAGAGGCAGACAGGUGUAUGGAGUCACCUGUAAAUUGAUUCAAGUGAGCCAGGAAAGCAGCAAAGGAAAGAGAAACCUGAGUGACGACGUGGUGGAGGAACAGGGCUGGAAAGAGGCUGCUGGCUGUCUGGCUUCGCAGCUCUGGCCUCCUAAUCAGCCUCGCUCUUGUCUCUGGUGUUCUCUGGCUCUUGUCCAUCUGUCUGUGUUUCUUUUUGCCAGCUAUUGACUAAUCUUUGCUGAAGCUGAGCUAGAAUUCUGGUGUUUAUAAGCAGGUAACUAGCUGAGCACUAGUUGAUAACUUUGGAGUUAGUGGAUAACCACAGGGCUGGGCUACUAAGCUUUUUCAGUUGAAAAAUAAAUAAAUAAAUAAAUAAACACCACACCCAGCUAAUUUUUGUAUUUUUAGUAGAGACAGGGUUUCACCGUGUUAGCCAGGAUGGACUCCAUCUCCUGACCUCGUGAUCCGCCUACCUCGGCCUCCCAAAGUGCUGGGAUUACAGGCGUGAGCCACCACGCCCGGUCACCUUUGUCCUGUUUUCUACAGGUUAGAAGCAAGGCACAAGUCAUACCUACAUUCAAGGAGAGGGGACCAUGCAAAGGAUAAACUGCAGGUGAAGAACUUGAGAGCUAUUUUAGAAGCUGCCUUCCACACUUUACAAUCUACUUUGCAGCUAUACUGAGCUCUUAGCAACUCCCUGGGCCUGCUGAGCACCUCUUGCCUUUCUGCCUUUGCGUAUGCUGUUCCCUCUGCCUGGAAUUCCAUGUCUUCUGCCUUUGCCCACCUCAUCUUAAGGCCUCUGCUUAGAUGCAAUUUCUUUGGGCUCUUAUUAGCAGCAUCCAAAUCUGUGCUGGUUUCUUCUCACGCUUACUCUGCAUCAUAAUUUUUCUGUUUACUCGUUAAUCCCCUCCCACUCCUGCCAGUACCUAAAGUAAAAUCUACACGGGCUUGGCACAUUGUGGAUGCUCAAUGAAGAUUUGUUAAAUGAGUGAAUGAUUAAAUGAAAUAAGCCCCAGCUUGGAACCCAGAGCUGUAAUUUCCGGUUGUGGUCCCUGUCCCCUGCCCAGGGGCUGUCUAAGGGCUCAUCUCUCCCAGGAGCCCCUGUAUCAUCUCAGUAACUAGACCAGUACCAUAUCCGACUUCCCCUGACUUUGAAAUAAUUUUCACCUGCAAUCAGGUGCGCUUCCCUAGAACCUCUCUCGCUGUUCUUUGCCUUUCUCCUUCCCCCGCCUUGUAUCUCCGUGGUCCUGCCAAAAAUCAGAAGCUCAUUAUUAAACCAGAAGCUUCCUUGCAUUAUCCCAGAGACUACAGACAGAAAAUAUUUGCUUCUAUCUCAACUGAGGACUGACAUAGUAAAGACUCCUUGAGAUGUUAGCUGUCAAGGAGGGGAAUAAAAGUUUUUCAUCUGCA